AGAUCAUCCCAGGCCACACAGAGGCCGGCUUGGUCACUAUGGAGGAGAUAGGCAUCUUGGUGGAGAAGGCUCAGGAUGAGAUCCCAGCACUGUCCGUGUCCCGGCCCCAGACCGGCCUGUCCUUCCUGGGCCCUGAGCCUGAGGACCUGGAGGACCUGUACAGCCGCUACAAGAAGCUGCAGCAAGAGCUGGAGUUCCUGGAGGUGCAGGAGGAAUACAUCAAAGAUGAGCAAAAGAACCUGAAAAAGGAAUUUCUCCAUGCCCAGGAGGAGGUGAAGCGAAUCCAAAGCAUCCCGCUGGUCAUCGGACAAUUUCUGGAGGCUGUGGAUCAGAAUACAGCCAUCGUGGGCUCUACCACAGGCUCCAACUAUUAUGUGCGCAUCCUGAGCACCAUCGAUCGGGAGCUGCUCAAGCCCAACGCCUCAGUGGCCCUCCACAAGCACAGCAAUGCACUGGUGGACGUGCUGCCCCCCGAAGCCGACAGCAGCAUCAUGAUGCUCACCUCAGACCAGAAGCCAGAUGUGAUGUACGCGGACAUCGGAGGCAUGGACAUCCAGAAGCAGGAGGUGCGGGAGGCCGUGGAGCUCCCGCUCACGCAUUUCGAGCUCUACAAGCAGAUCGGCAUCGAUCCCCCCCGAGGCGUCCUCAUGUAUGGCCCACCUGGCUGUGGGAAGACCAUGUUGGCAAAGGCGGUGGCACAUCACACAACAGCUGCAUUCAUCCGGGUCGUGGGCUCGGAGUUUGUACAGAAGUAUCUGGGUGAGGGCCCCCGCAUGGUCCGGGAUGUGUUCCGCCUGGCCAAGGAGAAUGCACCUGCCAUCAUCUUCAUAGACGAGAUUGAUGCCAUCGCCACCAAGAGAUUCGAUGCUCAGACAGGGGCCGACAGGGAGGUUCAGAGGAUCCUGCUGGAGCUGCUGAAUCAGAUGGAUGGAUUUGAUCAGAAUGUCAAUGUCAAGGUAAUCAUGGCCACAAACAGAGCAGACACCCUGGAUCCGGCCCUGCUACGGCCAGGACGGCUGGACCGUAAAAUUGAAUUUCCACUUCCUGACCGCCGCCAGAAGAGAUUGAUUUUCUCCACUAUCACUAGCAAGAUGAACCUCUCUGAGGAGGUUGACUUGGAAGACUAUGUGGCCCGGCCAGAUAAGAUUUCAGGAGCUGAUAUUAACUCCAUCUGUCAGGAGAGUGGAAUGUUGGCUGUCCGUGAAAACCGCUACAUUGUCCUGGCCAAGGACUUCGAGAAAGCAUACAAGACUGUCAUCAAGAAGGACGAGCAGGAGCAUGAGUUUUACAAGUGACCCUUCCCUUCCCUCCACCACACCACUCAGGGGCUGGGGCUUCUCUCGCACCCCCAGCACCUCUGUCCCAAAACCUCAUUCCCUUUUUUCUUUACCCAGGAUUGGUUUCUUCAAUAAAUAGAUAAGAUCGAAUCCAUUUAAUUUCUUCUUAGAAGUUUAACUCCUUUGGAGAAUGUGGGCCUUGAAUAGGAUCCUCUGGGUCCCUCUUAAUCUGACAGAUGAGCAGACGAGGUGCAUGGCCUGGGUUGCAGCUUGAGAGAACCAAAAUAUUCAAACCAGAUGACUUCCAAAAUGUGGGGAAAGGGAUGGAAAAUGAACCUGAGAUGGAGUCCUUAAUCACGGGAUAAAGCCCUGUGCAUCUCCCUCAUUUCCUACAGGUAAAAGACAGUAAAGAAAUUCAGGUCACAGGCCUUGGGAGUUCAUAGGAAGGAGAUGUCCAGUGCUGUCCAGUAGAACUUU